ACUCGCCGCAGAUCUCCCGGUGCCACCCGUUCCAGGGAGGCUGCUUGGUUUGGGAAGAUACUCCCCAGGGGUCUCCCCUUCCCUUGGGGGCGCAGCUGAGGACUGCGAGGUGCGUCCGAGGGCCAGAAAGCUGAGAUCGAUUCUGAGUUCAAGGAUCAAGUCUGCCCUCAAACCAUUUUACAGAUCGGGAAAUCCGAGACCCAGAGAAGGGAUACUCCCGCCCAAGGGCCACCGAGCCGAGAGAAGCCCGGGCCAGGGCUUUCUUCGCGUAUGUGGGAAUGCAGGCGCGAGCCCUUUGGGGGGCACAGUCCAUACGGGAGCUGAGGCCGAAGCCGGAGCACUAACUGUGCUGUCUAGGGGAUCGAGACGGCACUAGAGGGCUGGACUCCUUACUGCCUCAGUUUCCCCAGCACUACCUUUGUUGAGGAAACGGAGAUGGGGAUACUGGCCGAACGCGCGCCUGCUGAGACACAGUGCAACUGUAUUUAGACGCCCCGCACCUCCCCAAAUCUGAUCGAGGCUCCUUUUUUCAAGCACCCGCUAUCUCUCAGCCCUUUAAAAUCCGGCCCUGCCGUUCGAGUCUCUCGGCGUUCCAUUGGAAAGACUCGGGGCUCCAGCUCCCUUCUCUAGAAUGAACUGCUCUGACUGCCGCCCGGCUUUACCGGAGCUUUAACUGCGCAGGCGCAAGGGCAGCCAACCCGGUCGAUUCGCCGAUUCGCACGAGCUGUCAGAGCUGGGAAGAAGCUCAGUGAGGUUAGAGAACAGUCACUGAUGGUCCCAGAACCAAGAUUCAAGUCUAGAUCUCCCAGAUUCCAGGAUUCCCAGAUUGUAACUACCUCAAGAGUGUUUGCCCAGUGACUGCUGUCACAGUCCUGAAAGAAUGCACUGGGUUUUGAAAAGCAGAGUGUACUCUGCCUCUAACCUGCUUGUGCUGCUCAAUGACGGGAUCCUACGGAAGGAGCUUCGGAAAAAGUUGCCUGUGUCGCUGUCCCAGCAGAAGCUGCUGACAUGGCUGAGCGUGCUGGAGUGCGUGGAGGUGUUCAUGGAGAUGGGAGCUGCCAAGGUGUGGGGUGAAGUGGGCCGCUGGCUUGUCAUCGCCCUCGUCCAGCUGGCCAAGGCUGUACUGCGGAUGCUCCUGCUGCUCUGGUUCAAGGCUGGCCUCCAGACUUCACCCCCUAUCGUUCCACUGGACAGAGAGACCCAGGCACAGCCCCCGGAUGGUGACCACAGCCCUGGCAACCAUGAGCAGUCCUACGUGGGGAAGCGGUCAAACCGGGUGGUGCGAACCCUCCAGAACACGCCGUCCCUGCACUCCAGGCACUGGGGAGCUCCCCAGCAGCGGGAGGGACGGCAGCAGCAGCAUCACGAGGAGCUGAGUGCGACCCCCACCCCCCUGGGGCUGCAGGAGACCAUCGCAGAGUUUUUGUACAUUGCCCGGCCGCUGCUGCACUUGCUCAGCCUGGGCCUGUGGGGUCAGAGGUCGUGGAAACCCUGGCUCUUGGCUGGUGUUGUGGACGUGACCAGCCUGAGCCUCCUGAGUGACAGAAAGGGCCUGACCCGGAGGGAGCGGCGGGAGCUGCGGCGCCGGACCAUCCUGCUGCUCUACUACCUGCUGCGCUCUCCUUUCUAUGACCGCUUCUCCGAGGCCAGGAUCCUCUUCCUGCUCCAGUUGCUGGCCGACCACGUCCCUGGCGUUGGCCUGGUCACAAGGCCGCUCAUGGAUUACUUGCCCACCUGGCAGAAAAUCUACUUCUACAGUUGGGGCUGACAGACCUCCCGGAAGGAGGGUGUGGGGAGGGGUGGGGCAGGGAGCCCCUCUUCCCUAAUAAAACUGACUCCGGCAGCGUCCCAGCGUGCGGCCUCUCCGUGCCUACCGGCCAGGCCCCACACACAGCCCUGGUCGCCACCAGCGUUCCUCCCAGGACACCCUUGACUGCGCUCUCCUGUGACGAUGCCACUGCAGCCCGCACCUUGUCACUGCUGGGCCAAGAAGCCUUCACUAGGAGUGGGAUCCAGGCUCCUCUCCCACAGAAAGCGGUGACUUCACCUCAUGGAGCCCGGGAAGCUGCUCGCCUCGGCAGCCAUAGGAGCGAACACUGCUGCUCUCUCGCUGGCCCCUGGUGAGGACAGGAAGCCUGAACCCGGGUGAUGGCUGAACGCUGCCCAGCGUGUCUUCUGGCUGGGGCCCUCCGUCUGCCCCUUCUCCGCAGGGCCCUGUGGCUCUGGCAGCCCCAGGCCAUGGCGUUGCCAGCCUCCCUGUGACAGAGCCUGGUGAACAGUGAGCCUGGCUCCCACGCAAGUGGCACUUUAAGCCCUGCAUCCUCGGUUGAGAGUAAAAGGCUUUUCUCCCUUAGAAAAA